UGUCUCAAGAACCAGACAUAAAUAAGGAUUGUGAUAGAGAGGUUGAAGAAGAAAUGCAGAGGCACAGAAGUAAUAACGUGGGAAUAUCAGAAAACCUGACUGAUGGUGCCACUGCUGGCAAUGGUGAUGAUGGAUUAAUUCCACAAAGAAAGAGCAGAAAGCCUGAAAAUCAGCAAUUUCCUAGCACAGAGAAUGAAGAAUAUCAUAGGCCUGAAAAGAAAUUUAAUGAAAAGAACACGGUCAAAAGUGAAAUACAUUCAGUGGAUGACCUUGAUGACAUAACGUGGCCAUCUGAAAUAGCCUCAGAGGAUUACGAUUUGCCUUACCCUAAUUAUGAGACUUUUAUGUUGCUCACUGAACAAAUCAAAAUGGAUUUUAACGAUUCUGCUAGCCUAUCAAAAAUCCAGGAUGCAGUUCUUUCAGAUGAACACUUACUAGAACUUAAAAGUAAUCACUGUGAACAACUUACAAUAGAAAUUGAACAAAUGGAAAAUAUGAUUCAUGUACUACAAAAGAAGCUGUCUGAAACAAAAGAAACACAAUUACAGUUAGAACAUGAAAAAGAUGAAUGGGAGCAAGAACUCUCCACUUUGGGGGGAGGAGCCAAGAUGGCCGAAUAGGAACAGCUCCGGUCUACAGCUCCCAGUGUGAGUG